AGACGGAAGCGCGCUGGGACUGACACGUGGACUUGGGCGGUGCUGCCCGGGUGGGUCAGCCUGGGCUGGGAGGCAGCCCCGGGACACAGCUGUGCCCACGCCGUCUGAGCACCCCAAGCCCGAUGCAGCCACCCCCAGACGAGGCCCGCAGGGACAUGGCCGGGGACACCCAGUGGUCCAGGUGGAACCACCCUGUGUAUGCAUGACCCUGACAAGCAGGCGCCAGGACAGUCAGGAGGCCAGGCCCGAGUGCCAGGCAUGGACGGGGACGCUGCUGCUGGGCACAUGCCUUCUGUACUGCGCCCGCUCCAGCAUGCCCAUCUGCACCGUCUCCAUGAGCCAGGACUUCGGCUGGAACAAGAAGGAGGCCGGCAUCGUGCUCAGCAGCUUCUUCUGGGGCUACUGCCUGACACAGGUUGUGGGCGGCCACCUCGGGGAUCGGAUUGGGGGUGAGAAGGUCAUCCUGCUGUCAGCCUCUGCCUGGGGCUCCAUCACGGCCGUCACCCCACUGCUCGCCCACCUGAGCAGUGCCCACCUGGCCUUCAUGACCUUCUCACGCAUCCUCAUGGGCUUGCUCCAAGGGGUUUACUUCCCUGCCCUGACCAGCCUGCUGUCGCAGAAGGUGCGGGAGAGUGAGCGAGCCUUCACCUACAGCAUCGUGGGCGCCGGCUCCCAGUUUGGGACGCUGCUGACCGGGGCGGUGGGCUCCCUGCUCCUGGAAUGGUACGGCUGGCAGAGCAUCUUCUAUUUCUCCGGCGGCCUCACCUUGCUUUGGGUGUGGUACGUGUACAGGUACCUGCUGAGUGAAAAAGAUCUCAUCCUGGCCUUGGGUGUCCUGGCCCAAAGCCGGCCGGUGUCCAGGCACAACAGAGUCCCCUGGAGACGGCUCUUCCGGAAGCCUGCUGUCUGGGCAGCCGUCGUCUCCCAGCUCUCUGCAGCCUGCUCCUUCUUCAUCCUCCUCUCCUGGCUGCCCACCUUCUUCGAGGAGACCUUCCCCGACGCCAAGGGCUGGAUCUUCAACGUGGUUCCUUGGUUGGUGGCGAUUCCGGCCAGUCUAUUCAGCGGGUUUCUCUCUGAUCAUCUCAUCAAUCAGGGUUACAGAGCCAUCACGGUGCGGAAGCUCAUGCAGGGCAUGGGCCUUGGCCUCUCCAGCGUCUUUGCUCUGUGCCUGGGCCACACCUCCAGCUUCUGUGAGUCUGUGGUCUUUGCAUCAGCCUCCAUCGGCCUCCAGACCUUCAACCACAGUGGCAUUUCUGUUAACAUCCAGGACUUGGCCCCGUCCUGCGCCGGCUUUCUGUUUGGUGUGGCCAACACAGCCGGGGCCUUGGCAGGUGUCGUGGGUGUGUGUCUAGGCGGCUACUUGAUGGAGACCACGGGCUCCUGGACUUGCCUGUUCAACCUUGUGGCCAUCAUCAGCAACCUGGGGCUGUGCACCUUCCUGGUGUUUGGACAGGCUCAGAGGGUGGACCUGAGCUCUACCCAUGAGGACCUCUAGCUCCCAACCCCACAGCCUCUCCAAGGACCCAGGCGCCAGCAGCCCCAGGACACAGGGGACUCAGUGUGUGGGACUUGGUCACUCCAUGUCAGACACACGAGCAGAGAGGAACACAAACCACUGUGGAGCCUGAAGCUCCUUAAGAAGAGUCCACAACAGCUGGUGGGAGGGUGGGGUGGGCCUGGGUCCAGACCAGGCUCGCUGCUCUCUGGGCCUCAGUUUCCCCACCUGCCAGCGGGCUCGGCCCUGUCCUCCUCACAGGCUGGUGUGGCCGUCAGGGUGGGUGGGGUUAUUGUUAGUAGGCGCAGCCUCAUUCCCACCACGAUCUGUUCCGCGUGGUUCCCGCCAAACCUCCCUCGGUCGCCGUGUUCUCCGCAAGCCUCCUGCAGCGCCCGCCUGCCAAUGUGAGGCUGGCACCAGGCUGCAGCCUCCCCAAUCCCAGCCCACUUUGCUGUGUCUCUGGCGGGCUGUCCUCCUUGGUGGGAGCUGUCCUGCACACUGUAGGAUGCUUAAAGGUAUCCCUGGCCUCCACCCACCCCUAGCCAGCAGCUCCCAGUCAGACAACAGCCAGAAAUGUCUCCAGACUCUGCCCAGCCUCCCCAGGUAGCCACCCUCGAGACACGACCUCAGAGUCUCUGUGUCUCCUAGAAGCCUGACAGAGACCCCCAGGGCAGUGGGUGGGUGGCGGGCUAGAGACCCUUGCCUGUGUCCGGGACCCUGGCGCCGCUCUCCCCUCCUGUGGAUCCCUCCGCACUAACAGUGUUCUCAGUGGGCAGACGCCUGGGCACCCCUUGGGCCCUGCCCAGCAUGGCCAUGGCGCAGGCUCUCGAACCCGCAUGGCUUUCCCAGGCCUGGUGAUUCUGCUCUCCAGGGACGGUUGGCACCUUCCUCGGGGGCGGGCCCCACGCACCCCAGAACACACAGACCCACCUUUCUGGCGUUCUUUCUACCUCCCUUUUCGUUGCCUGAGGAGCUGGUGGUUUCAUGAGUUAAUGAUACAUCUUGCAAGGUGUACACAUAGAGAAAAAAACCUAAAAAUGUGGAAAAGCACGCCAAAGCCUUAUUUAAAUAAUAACUAUUAAACUAUUCAAAAAGAAGACUGUUAUUUUAUUUAACACCUUUGUUUUUUAAGAAUGAACACGUGUUAAAGACUUUCUGUAACUAAUUUCAUGAGGAAACGAGUGACACGUUGGAAUCAGGUCAAAGGAGAAUCCCAGGAACGGACUCCUAGGCCGGGAGUGUUGAAAUGAGCAUGCCAGCAGAGCCAGGCUGGGUUUCGGGGUUCCUUUGCCGCCAGGGGUCCUGCGUGUCCACAGAUGACAGCGAUGUACCCUGCUAUCAGCUGUCCACCCAGCUUUCCCAAGAUGUGGGGCCCCCAUGGAGUCAGACAGCCCAGCUGUGCUGUGGAAAGACAAAGUGGAGUUUUGCACUUGAGCACAAAUGUUCCCCUACAAUCUCUCCAGUUUCGGUCAGCCCAACCCUGUGGCACCAUGGGUACAGCCUAGAGCAUCACCCCCACAGAGGCUUCGGGACGGUCCUGCUGGACUGCUGGACGCUGCUGUGGGGUCUUGGGGCAGGAGGGGCUUCCAGAAGCCUGGCAGUUGCUGUCUGGAGGCCAGGAAGCCAAGCCCAGGAAGCCCACCUGCGGCUGAGUUCAGAGGUGGGGCCUGUGCGUUGUGAAUGAAUUGCUGUCUCUCUCCUCCUCAUCUUGCACUAAAUCUACAUAACUUAAAAUUUACCAUUUUAGCCAUUUUUAAGUGCACGGUUCUGUGGCAUUAGGUACAUUCGCAUUGUGCAGCCACCGCCACCCUCCGCCUUCAGAACUUUCUCAUCUUCCCAAACCGAAGCUCUGUGCUCAUUAAAGGCUAGCUCCCCGUUGCUCUCCCCCAGCCCCGGCAACCCCAUUCCACUUUGUGUCUCGACCGUAAGUGUGGCUGCUCUGGGACCAGUGCCAGUGGGCGCACGCUGGGUUUGCCUACGUCUGGCUUACUUCACUCAGCAGAGUGUCCUUCGGUUUUAUCAGUUUUGUCACAAGUGUCAGCAUUUUUCUCAUUUUUAAGGCUGAAUAAAAUAUUGUGUGGAUAA